AGAUAAUGGUCUCCGUGGCCAAGUCCCAGUCCUGCUGUCCCAAGGGACUCCGGGGUCAGGUGGAGCAGGCAGGGCAGUCUGCCACGGGCUCCCCAACUGAAGCCACUCUGGGGAGGGUCCGGCCACCAGAAAAUUUGCCCAGCUUUGCUGCCUGUUGGCCAUGGGUGACCUCUCAUCUUUGACCCCCGGAGGGUCCAUGGGUCUCCAAGUAAACAGAGGCUCCCAGAGCUCCCUGGAGGGGGCUCCUGCCACCGCCCCGGAGCCUCACAGCCUGGGCAUCCUCCAUGCCUCCUACAGCGUCAGGUAAGGCAGAGCCCUUGCUGCUGCUGCUCCCCCAGGAGUGCGGGGCCCGGCGCUCACCCCUCUGCUGCCUUUCUUCACUCUUUAAGUGCCAGUCUGGGCACUUCGGGCUCCCUCUUUAGUGGAUCGGGUGGAGAGAGGAGAGGGAGAAGGGCUGUGCUGGGAAACAUGGAGCGACAGUGAAUGGCCCCUCCCCCUGCCCAGGGAAGGGCCUGGGCAUAAACAAAGUGGCAGCAGUGCCCUGCCAACCCAGUGUCUACGGCCUGCCCUCUGUGGAUGGGAAUGGGGGUACUGCGAAUGCAAGGAGUCUUGAAACCUGGUGAAAGAAUGCAGGGACAGCCACCUCGCAGCCAAACGGACAGGACAUUCAGAGCAACUCCAGCACAGGCCCCCUCCCUACGUGGCAGACAGCCUCAGUCGCUAUCUGCCAGGUUCUACAGAGGAGGGCGCAGAGACUGAAACACGUUAGGAGCCUGUCCGGAGACUACUGGGGUGGGGCACAGCCACCGCGUGAGGCCCUGGUGGGACAUCACAUCUUGCCGGCAGCAGUGGACCAGGCAGAUCCUCAAAGAUGUCUCCUUGUACGUGGAGAGCGGGCAGAUCAUGUGCAUCCUAGGAAGCUCAGGCUCCGGGAAAACCACGCUGCUGGACGCCAUGUCCGGGAGGCUGGGGCGCGCGGGGACCUUCCUGGGGGAGGUGUAUGUGAACGGCCGGGCGCUGCGCCGGGAGCAGUUCCAGGACUGCUUCUCCUACGUCCUGCAGAGCGACACCCUGCUGAGCAGCCUCACCGUGCGCGAGACGCUGCACUACACCGCGCUGCUGGCCAUCCGCCGCGGCAAUCCCGGCUCCUUCCAGAAGAAGGUGGAGGCCGUCAUGGCAGAGCUGAGUCUGAGCCAUGUGGCAGACCGACUGAUUGGCAACUACAGCUUGGGGGGCAUUUCCACGGGUGAGCGGCGCCGGGUCUCCAUCGCAGCCCAGCUGCUCCAGGAUCCUAAGGUCAUGCUGUUUGAUGAGCCAACCACAGGCCUGGACUGCAUGACUGCUAAUCAGAUUGUCGUCCUCCUGGUGGAACUGGCUCGCAGGAACCGAAUUGUGGUUCUCACCAUUCACCAGCCCCGUUCUGAGCUUUUUCAGCUCUUUGACAAAAUUGCCAUCCUGAGCUUCGGAGAGCUGAUUUUCUGUGGCACGCCAGCGGAAAUGCUUGAUUUCUUCAAUGACUGCGGUUACCCUUGUCCUGAACAUUCAAACCCUUUUGACUUCUAUAUGGACCUGACGUCAGUGGAUACCCAAAGCAAGGAACGGGAAAUAGAAACCUCCAAGAGAGUCCAGAUGAUAGAAUCUGCCUACAAGAAAUCAGCAAUUUGUCAUAAAACUUUGAAGAAUAUUGAAAGAAUGAAACACCUGAAAACGUUACCAAUGGUUCCUUUCAAAACCAAAGAUUCUCCUGGAGUUUUCUCUAAACUGGGUGUUCUCCUGAGGAGAGUGACAAGAAACUUGGUGAGAAAUAAGCUGGCAGUGAUUACGCGUCUCCUUCAGAAUCUGAUCAUGGGUUUGUUCCUCCUUUUCUUCGUUCUGCGGGUCCGAAGCAAUGUGCUAAAGGGUGCUAUCCAGGACCGCGUAGGUCUCCUUUACCAGUUUGUGGGCGCCACCCCGUACACAGGCAUGCUGAACGCUGUGAAUCUGUUUCCCGUGCUGCGAGCUGUCAGCGACCAGGAGAGUCAGGACGGCCUCUACCAGAAGUGGCAGAUGAUGCUGGCCUAUGCACUGCACGUCCUCCCCUUCAGCGUUGUUGCCACCAUGAUUUUCAGCAGUGUGUGCUACUGGACGCUGGGCUUACAUCCUGAGGUUGCCCGAUUUGGAUAUUUUUCUGCUGCUCUCUUGGCCCCCCACUUAAUUGGUGAAUUUCUAACUCUUGUGCUACUUGGUAUCGUCCAAAAUCCAAAUAUAGUCAACAGUGUAGUGGCUCUGCUGUCCAUUGCGGGGGUGCUUGUUGGAUCUGGAUUCCUCAGAAACAUACAAGAAAUGCCCAUUCCUUUUAAAAUCAUCAGUUAUUUUACAUUCCAAAAAUAUUGCAGUGAGAUUCUUGUAGUCAAUGAGUUCUACGGACUGAAUUUCACUUGUGGCAGCUCAAAUGUUUCUGUGACAACUAAUCCAAUGUGUGCCUUCACUCAAGGAAUUCAAUUCAUUGAGAAAACCUGCCCAGGUGCAACAUCUAGAUUCACAAUGAACUUUCUGAUUUUGUAUUCAUUUAUUCCAGCUCUUGUCAUCCUAGGAAUAGUUGUUUUCAAAAUAAGGGAUCAUCUCAUUAGCAGGUAGUGAAAGCCAUGGCUGGGAAAAUGGAAGUGAAGCUGCCGACUGUGCAUGACUGCUCUGAACGUCUGAAAUGAGAGUGCCAUGUAUUUCUUUCUUGACAGGACAUCUCAAGUCUUUUAACCAUUAAGACUCCAUUUGUGCCUCUUGGAUCCAAGCAGGCCUUGAAUGCAAUGGAAGUGGUUUAUAGUCCCUUGCUCUUACAACUUGCAGGGACAUGUGGUUAUUUGGAAAUUGUGACUGAGCGGACCCAAGAAUGUAAAUAAUAUUCAUAAACCUAUGGGAGACUCGUGUGACUAUUUUUUUUCCUUGUUCUAGGCACAGAAAAAAAUAGGUCAGCUUAAAAAUAUGUUUACAUUGGAUAAAGGAUUAGGCAAAAAUAAAAUGUUUCAAGGAUUCCUGACCAUAAGUGACAGAGAAAGAGAGUUGUGGGUUUAGAUGAAGCAAGGUUAUCAUGCAGAAUUGGGUAAGAAUGCUUCUGUUCCUGGAAGACCCAGAGUUAAAUGCAGAUGUCCACACGAGGGGUCGGAGUUACCUGAUCACAUCGAGAGAGUGCUGGGCAGAUGGAUGGUGAGCACCACUGCUACAGAGCACCCAGUGAUUUUACUGAGGAUUAAAAUAAAAAACCGUAGGAAUGGGCUCAACAGUGA